AUGGCUCUCCUUUUGACACUAACAUCACCAGACCUGGAGGGUACCUGGGACACCAGAGACAAGGAUGGCUUCAAAGCCCAGGAGGGGCCGCCCCUGGCUGUACCUGAAUUUCCUGUGUGUGGACUGUACCGGAUCUACGGAGUCUGUGGCUCUUUCAGCUCCUUCUUCAUCAUCCGGUGCAGCCUUUGUGCUCUGGAGACCCUCAAAUCACCCCAACAUGAUCCCUUAGAGAUACCUGAACAGUCCCUCAAACUCAUACCCCUGGUGUCUGGGAAAAGGGAACUCACAAGGGGCCAGAAAGCUGGAGAGAAGCCCCUGGCUGCAGGACCCGGGGAGGAGGAACUGCUCCGGGGCUCAGCCCCUCAUGCUCAGGACACUCAGAGUGAGGAACUGCCACCCUCCUGCACCAUCUCAGGAGAGAAGAAGCCGCCAGCAGUCUCUGGAGAAGCCACCGGGGCUGAUGCUGGGAGACUGUGCCCGCCCCCCCGCUCCAGGGCUCCCCACAAAGACAGAACUCUAGCCCGCUCCAGGCCCCAGACUCAGGGGGAAGAUUGUUCCCUCCCAGUGGGAGAGGUGAAGAUAGGAAAGAGGUCCUAUUCUCCAGCCCCCGGGAAGCAGAAAAAGCCUAAUGCCAUGGGUCUGGCCCCAACAUCAUCUCCGGGUGCCCCUAACUCAGCCCGUGCCACACACAACCCAGUGCCCUGUGGGUCAGGCCGGGGGCCCUGCCACCUGGCCAAUCUCCUCAGUACAUUGGCGCAGAGCAACCAAAACAGAGACCACAAGCAGGGGCCCCCGGAAGUGACCUGCCAAAUUAGGAAAAAGACACGAACCCUAUACCGCUCAGAUCAGCUGGAGGAGCUAGAGAAGAUAUUCCAAGAAGACCACUAUCCUGACAGUGAUAAACGCCGAGAGAUUGCCCAGACGGUGGGGGUGACCCCCCAGCGCAUCAUGGUGUGGUUCCAGAAUCGCCGGGCCAAGUGGCGAAAAAUGGAGAAACUGAAUGGGAAAGAAAGCAAGGACAAUCCUGCAGCCCCUGGCCCUGCCAGCAGUCAAUGCAGCUCUGCAGCUGAGAUCCUACCUGCUGUGCCCAUGGAGCCAAAGCCUGACCCUUUCCCUCAGGAGUCCCCUCUGGAUACCUUUCCAGAGCCCCCCAUGCUGCUGACUUCUGACCAGACUUUGGCCCCCACCCAACCCAGUGAGGGUGCUCAGAGGGUGGUGACCCCCCCACUCUUCAGCCCCCCACCUGUGCGAAGGGCCGAUCUUCCUUUCCCCCUUGGCCCUGUCCACACCCCCCAACUGAUGCCACUGCUGAUGGAUGUUGCUGGCAGUGACAGCAGCCACAAGGACGGCCCCUGUGGGUCCUGGGGGACAAGCAUCACCCUGCCACCCCCCUGUUCAUAUUUGGAGGAGCUGGAGCCCCAGGAUUACCAACAGAGCAACCAGCCAGGACCCUUCCAGUUCUCCCAGGCUCCACAGCCCCCGCUUUUCCAGUCCCCUCAGCCCAAGUUGCCCUACCUCCCCACUUUCCCCUUCUCCAUGCCCAGUUCACUGACGCUUCCACCGCCCGAAGACUCUCUCUUUAUGUUUCCCUGUGGCCCCAGCGGGGGCACAUCGCAGGGCUAUUGCCCAGGUGCCUCCUCAGGACAGAUCCUGAUGCAACCACCUGCUGGGAAUAUAGGUACAGCCUCCUGGAGUGACCCCUGUUUGCCAGAGCUGCCCUUCCCUGGUCCGUUCUGCCCACAAGCUCUGGGGCAUCCCCCAGGAGGGGAUGGCUACUUUCCUGAUCUAUUUCCAACUCCCUGCCCCCAGGCUCUGGGCAGGCAGCCUUCGUCAGCUCUCUCAUGGAUGCCUGAAGGGGCCAGACCAGGGACUGGGCCCUUACUCAGCAAGGCAAAAGAGGAACCACCAGCUGCUUCCCUGGAUCAGCCCUCAGCACUGGAGGAGGCCAGAGGGGAUGACAAGAAUAGCCAUGUCCCCUAGUUGGGGGGUCAAAGAGUGAAAAGAGGCUGCUUGGGUGGGAUAGGAUUGGGCUCGCUGAGAGGACAGGGGUUGGGGGUUUGGGAAAGAGUGUGGACUCUGUAGACUGAGGGGAGAGUUAGACGUUUCCCCUGUGUAGGCUCGUCUUGUUGAUAUGAGAAGGAAGAAAGAGGGCUGGCGCUUCCCUUUUCUUCACACUCUGUGUGGGGGUCCUGAAGGAAGCAGGUGGCCUGUGUUACUUCUGAAUGUUGUAUCAGGUGUUUUUGUUUGUUUCCUAUCCUUGCUUGACAAAUGAGCUGGAGUGUCCACCGUAAGCAGUAAACUAGUCCGUCCUGCGGUUUUC